AGUCCCAGCGGCGCAGCCACCCAUGCGCGCGCGCUCGCAAGACCACCAGCGCCCAGAGCCCCAGUCUGAGGCUUGGCGCCGGGGGUCUGCGGGCGAGGGGAGCUCUCUACGUGCGAGGGGCUAGCGGGAGCCGGCACAAGAGGGUCGAGGAGCCAGGAACCCCAAACGUCCGGCGCCAGGCGCUAGCCAAGCUGCUGCGCGCCCCGGCGCCCAGCUGGCUCGGGGACAGCCGCUGGGUGUCGGAGACCGGAGCUAGCGGAUUGCAGCGGAAAAGCAAAGAUGUCACACUGGAUCCUUGGCCUCCAGGGUCCAUUAAGGUGAGAAUAAGAUCUCUGGGCUGGCUGGAACUAGCCUAAGACUGAAAAGCAGCCAUGGACAUGGCGGAUGAGCCACUCAAUGGAAGCCACACAUGGCUAUCCAUUCCAUUUGACCUCAAUGGCUCUGUGGUGUCAACCAACACCUCAAACCAGACAGAGCCGUACUAUGACCUGACAAGCAAUGCAGUCCUCACAUUCAUCUAUUUUGUGGUCUGCAUCAUUGGGUUGUGUGGCAACACACUUGUCAUUUAUGUCAUCCUCCGCUAUGCCAAGAUGAAGACCAUCACCAACAUUUACAUCCUCAACCUGGCCAUCGCAGAUGAGCUCUUCAUGCUGGGUCUGCCUUUCUUGGCUAUGCAGGUGGCUCUGGUCCACUGGCCCUUUGGCAAGGCCAUUUGCCGGGUGGUCAUGACUGUGGAUGGCAUCAAUCAGUUCACCAGCAUCUUCUGCCUGACAGUCAUGAGCAUCGACCGAUACCUGGCUGUGGUCCACCCCAUCAAGUCGGCCAAGUGGAGGAGACCCCGGACGGCCAAGAUGAUCACCAUGGCUGUGUGGGGAGUCUCUCUGCUGGUCAUCUUGCCCAUCAUGAUAUAUGCUGGGCUCCGGAGCAACCAGUGGGGGAGAAGCAGCUGCACCAUCAACUGGCCAGGUGAAUCUGGGGCUUGGUACACAGGGUUCAUCAUCUACACUUUCAUUCUGGGGUUCCUGGUACCCCUCACCAUCAUCUGUCUUUGCUACCUGUUCAUUAUCAUCAAGGUGAAGUCCUCUGGAAUCCGAGUGGGCUCCUCUAAGAGGAAGAAGUCUGAGAAGAAGGUCACCCGAAUGGUGUCCAUCGUGGUGGCUGUCUUCAUCUUCUGCUGGCUUCCCUUCUACAUAUUCAACGUUUCUUCCGUCUCCAUGGCCAUCAGCCCCACCCCAGCCCUUAAAGGCAUGUUUGACUUUGUGGUGGUCCUCACCUAUGCUAACAGCUGUGCCAACCCUAUCCUAUAUGCCUUCUUGUCUGACAACUUCAAGAAGAGCUUCCAGAAUGUCCUCUGCUUGGUCAAGGUGAGCGGCACAGAUGAUGGGGAGCGGAGUGACAGUAAGCAGGACAAAUCCCGGCUGAAUGAGACCACGGAGACCCAGAGGACCCUCCUCAAUGGAGACCUCCAAACCAGUAUCUGAACUGCUUGGGGGGUGGGAAAGAACCAAGCCAUGCUCUGUCUACUGGCAAUGGGCUCCCUACCCACACUGGCUUCCUGCCUCCCACCCCUCACACCUGGCUUCUAGAAUAGAGGAUUGCUCAGCAUGAGUCCAAUUCAGAGAACGGUGUUUGAGUCAGCUUGUCUGAUUGAAUGAUAAUGUGCUAAAUUGAUUACCUCCCCCUUAAAGCGAACACUGAAAUGCAGGUAGACAAUUCAAAGUCUGGAGAAGAGGGAUCAUGCCUGGAUAUGAUCUUUAGAAACAACAAAAAUAGAAAAAAAUAAGUAUCUGUGUGUUUGUGUAUUGAAAACUCAAUAUGUAAUCUUGUGUUUUUAUAUGUAUACUUGUAUAUUCCUAUUUAUUCUCUGUAUAGGCAUUACCUACGUUCCUGUGUUUACAUACACAAGUAGCAAAUUCGAGUAUGCAUAGUGUAGAUGGACAUUUGCCACAACACACUGCCCGCAGAAAUGGACUUACCGUGAAGCCAAUAAAGUUCAAGCUUCAGGGAUCUCUCUUGCACGGGCCUUGCCAAGGCCCAGGAGGGACUUGGGCAGUAUGUUCAUGUGGUCAUAUGUUUUUGUAAAAAAUUGUGAAAGUAAGAUAUGUUUGUAUUGUUUUUCUUAAAGAGGAACCUCGUAUAAGCUUCAAGCCUCACAAACCUUCUAGCCUCUGCCCUUGGGGAUUUGCUUCAUUAAUUUCAGGCAAGUGAGGUCAAUGUAAGAAGGGAAAGGGAGAAGAUAUUUGAAGAACCAGAAUGUAAAUUCAUGUGUUUCCACUUCUCAGAUAUAGUCAGAGAAUUAUUCAUUUGCCCAAAAGGACUUAAGUGGUUGUGGUCAUCCAUCAUUGUAUUUAUCAAGACAAAGCCAACUUUGUUAUAAGAUUGCAUUUUUUUCUUUUCAAAUUGCUUUAGUUUUUCUUAGGGAGCUAUGAGGGGGAAAAAUCACUAACAUGAAAGGCAAAAAAUGGACUAUGAUUCCUGUGGGGAAACAAUUUCAUUCUCUCCAUCGUGAAAAUAAGUGAAUAAGAGUGAAGCAAAAUUACACCUUUAUGAGAAACCAUAAAAUUGUUUUUAUUUUUCAGGCCAGACAUAGCUUCCUAAUGAAAGAAAAUGGAAAUGUAAUUCGACGACUCCUCAAAGGGGACUUUAGAGGACUUCAUACAAAGCUGGGCAUUAAGAAAACCACAAUGCAUGGCCGGGCGUGGUGGCUUACACCUGUAAUCCCAGCACUUUGGGAGGCCGAGGUGGGUGGAUCACCCGAGGUCAGGAGUUCGAGACCAGCCUGGCCAACAUGGUGAAACCCCAUCACUACUAAAAAUAUGUAAAUUAGUCGGGCGUGGUGUCACGUGCCUGUAAUCCUAGCUGCUCGGGAGGCUGAGGCAGGAGAAUCACUUGAACUUGGGAGGUGGAGGUUGCAGUAAGCUGAGAUUGUGCCACUGCACUCUAGCCUGAGCAACAAGAGCAAAACUCAGUCUCAAAAAAAAAAAAAAAAAAAAAAAAAAAAAAAAAAAAGGAAAACCACAAUGCGUACUAAAGACCAGAAGACAUUGUUCACAAAACAAAAGCACCCUCACCUGCCAAUGAAUAUGCAGCGUGCAGGGGGUGUGGUGUGAGUGUUGGUGGGGCCCCACCUCUCGGAGAUACUGCUGUGCUGCCUUCCUCACUGACUGUAUACAUAGUAACUGUCAUAUCUUUAAUGCCAUGGACUCACUGAGCCGCUCUGCAAGGACUAUUGUAGACAGGCACUUCACACCAUAAAGUGGCAUUUUUUUCGUUCCCCAAACUGACAUUUACAAGCGAUAAGAAAAGAGACAAUAUCCAUUUCAUUGACUGAUCAUUUUCUAGAGUAUGAAGAAAUACACACCUGGGUGUCUGCAAGGAUGUCAUCAUCUUUGGGUUUCAUCUGAGAGCAUCACUCAGCAUCUCACACAUAGAUGUUACCAUAUUUUUAAAUGAGCUUUCCUCAUCCGGCUCCCUAAGCAAGCGCUGUUGGCCGGUGGGAGUGACUAAGUGCUCCACCUGUGGGUGUCCUUCUUAAUGUGCUGCUUUUGUUCUGUAUAAAUUCACACCACCUCACUCCCAAAAGUACUUCCUGUGGCUCAGAAAAAUAUGUUCAAUAAGAUUUUGGAUAGAUAAAUCCAUACAAAAAUAAAAAGAGGUAUAGUUAUAAAACAAGACUACAGAAAAAGUUGUGGCAGAAAUUGCAUGCAGGAAAAUCCCACACCAUUAGUAAAAGUAAGGUCAACUGUAAGUUCAGCUCAGGGCUUCCUAGCAGCCAUGUUUAGCGAAGUGUGAUUUUUUUUUUUAAACAAAAACAAGCAAAGAUUUGGAAGAAAAUGCUUUAGACCUAACUUUACAAUUAUUAUAACAUAAGAUGUUCCAGGGUCCUUGAAUAAAUGCUGAGUUUUAGGGAAAUGAUUCCAAGGGACCAAGAAUUGGUAGAAAUAAUUUCAAGGCAGAGAAGACUAAUUCUACAGGCCGGGCGUGGUGGCUUAUGCCUGUAAUCCCACACUUUGGGAGGCUGAGGUGGGUGGAUUGCCUGAGGUCAAGAGUUCAAGACCAGCCUGGCCAACAUGGUGAAACCCUGUCUCUACUAAAAAUACAAAAAAUUACCCAGGCAUGGUGGCGGGCGCCUGUAAUCCCAGCUACUUGGGAGGCUGAGACAGGAGAAUGGCUUGAACCCAGGAGGUGGAGAUUGCGGUGAGCUGAGAUCGUGCCAUUGCACUCCAGCCUGGGCAACAAGAGCGAAACUUCAUCUCAAAAAAAAAAAACAAAGACUAAUUCUAUAGUACCCAUGACCCUGCAACCAGAGAAACUGCCUGUAGGGAGGCCAGAGUCCAAAGCAGCCACCUGUAACCUGAAAAUGAAACGCAGACCCAGGCAUCUGUGGGUCUUCAUCAGCAGGAUGACCAUUCUAAGGCUAAAAGACAGGCCUUUAAAUCUGAUGCUAUAAUUCCAUCCAAAUACACAGUUAGGUUUCUACCAUAGGGAAAGCUAUUCUCUACUUUUUGAAGUAUCUGUUUCAAAGAUAACUUGCUCUCUGGUUCUCUUUUAUCUAAAAGAGAGAAUCAACAUGCUAAUUUAAAGGUUAACAUCAUUUUAAUUCAAAAAUUUUAGUCUCCAUUCCAUAUUUAAUGAUGAAGACAAAUCUGCUGGGUGCUGGGAGGGAAUAAAAAGUAAUGCACCCCAUUGAUUUCAGAGUAUCUGAUCACUUGGGUUAUGCAAGCUGCUACUUACCCGCCAUUAGCAUGGGUAGUUAAGUGCUGAUUAAACCUAAGUGGACUCAGUGAAAAAGAUAUUGGGAAAAAUAAUAUGAUAUUGUGGCCUAUGUUGAAUGAUGUUAGCUUGUGUUUCAGUAACAGAGUUGGGUAAUACUGGACGUGUAGAUGAAGCUUUAGCAGGGCUGGGCACGGUGGCUCAUGCCUGUAAUCCCAGCACUUUGGGAGGCUGAGGCGGGUGGAUUACCUGAGGUCAGGAGUUCAAGACCAGCCUGGCCAACAUGGGGAAACCCUGUCUCUACUAAGAAUACAAAAAUUAGCUGGGUGUGGUGGCGUGUGCCUGUAAUCCCAGCUACUCAGGAGGCUGAGACAGGAGAAUCGCUUGAACCCGGGAGGCGAAGGUUGCAGUGAGCCAAGAUCGCGCCACUGCACUUCAGCCUGGGUGACAGCACAAGACUCCAUCUCAAAAAAAAAAAAAAAAGGAAGAAGAAAAAGAAACUUAAGUGGGGUUCAUACAUAGCAUGGCAGAGGGACACUGGAGAAUAAAAUGGCAUGCAGAGAGGAACACGCGGGCCAGUGGAUGAGGCUUCUAGACCUGGCAGUGAACUGGAGUCUAUUUGCUUACACAAAUUUAACCUUCUCUCCAUGAUGGAAUACAAGUGUUUCUUGCCAAAACUCGCAGCCCCAGCUGCCCUAGAUGAGGAGCACCGUGCUGGAAAAGUGCACAGGCUGAUCACAGAGACAGGUAGGAAGCAAUGGACUGUUAAAAUGCAUGUUCCGGGCUGGGGAUGGUGGCUCACACCUGUGAUCUCAGCACUUUGGGAGGCCGAGGCUGGGGAAUCGCUUGAGCCCAGGAUUUUGAGACUAGCCUAGGCAAUAUGGUGAGACCCUGCCCUUAAAAAAAAAAAAGAAAAGAAAAGAAAAGAAAAAAAGAUUCAUAUUCCUGAUCAGCUCUGAAUGUGACUAUUCAAUGAAGACAGUAAAGUUACAGUGUAAGGCACACAUGACCUUUGGCCUUGCUAAAGAAGAGUGGCUGAAGGUCUAGCAAAUUAAUGCUUGUCUUAGGUUACCUGUUGAUUUAAAAACAACAACAACAAAAACCCAUAAAAAUAGUAAAAUAUAAAAACAAAUUAGUGUUUUAUAGACCCUGGGGAAAAGAAUUUUCAGCAAAGUACAAAAAUUUAAAGCAUUCCUUUCUUUAAUUUUGUAAUUCUUUACUGUAGAACAGCUCAAAAUAUCAGUUCUGUUUUAAGUAACAGAAUUGAUAACUGAGCAGGGAAACGUAAUUUGGAUUGUAAAAUUCUUGCUUUAAUAAAAAUUCUUUAAACAGUCAAAAUAGAAAGAAAGAAAGAAAGGUGGCAAGAGAAUUAUCAAAAGUUUCCAUAGAUGGUUGGGAAGAUCUGAUUAGUGUUUCCAAAAUGCUUAUCAUUCUAAGAAUCCCAAUAGCUGGCAAGCCAAGCAGUGGAACUUAUAGUAACAACAAUCAAUCACUUGUCUCAUCCCACAUUUUUGCCAAAUUCAAAAACACCAAAUUUCCCAUCAAAUGUUCUGUCAGAGUAAACCUUUACCUAAGUGCUUGUUUUGCUUUUAAUAUGUGAAUUUCUGGGAACAUUCCCAUGGGCAGCCUCUAAUUUUUUUUUUUUUUUUUUGAGACAGAGUUUCGCUUUUUCACCCAGGCUGGAGCGCAGUGGCACGAUCUUGGCUCACUGCAACCUCCACCUACCGGAUUCAAGUGAUUCUCCUGCCUCAGCCUCCCAAGUAGCAGGGACUACAGGCACGUGCCACCACGCCCAGCUAAUUUUUGUAUUUUUAGUGGAGAUGGGUUUUUGCCAUGUUGGCCAGGCAGGUCUUGAACUCUUGACCUCAGGUGAUCCGCCUGCCUCAGUGUCCCAAAGUGUUGGGAUUACAGGCACGAGCCACCGCGCUCAGCCAAUUUUUCCUCAACUCUCUCUUUCCUGGACGGGCUGCGUUGGGGGGAGGUGCAGGGAAAGAACACCUCUUUGCUUAGACAUUGGUGUCGACAGUGGGGAUACUAAGUUCAUCUCCUGAUCCUGCUAGGCCUGGAAGCAGGAAAGAAAUGUCCUGGUUAGAGAUAAAAUUGUUCUAUCCUUUUAGAAAAGCCUGUUAAGGAAUAUGAUGCAAAGCCACCUUCGACGAAAUCUGAAAUGAUACCCCACAGCCUUGUCCACCCCAAUUAUUCAGUGACAGGGCUCCAGUUGCUUAAGCCAUAGAGAAGGCCCCUUUGCAGUGGGAGUCACUGAAGACAGAAAGGGAAGCCCAGGAUGAACCCAGUCCUAAGGGCUGCUGGGGGCCACCAAAUAAGACUGUUUUAGCCCUGGACACAGAGGGAGACACAGUCAUCCCAGAUCCUUACAAAGAAUACAUUGCCAAGGACCCCGAAGGAAAUCUGCUUGUCUUAAGAGAGGAAGACCCACGACCAGCUCUCUGGGACUACCUGUCAACUCAGCAGGUGCAGCCAGGGAGCAGCCAUGCUUCUUCUGCCCUCCCAGUAGGCUGGGCUAUCAGUUCCUGGGAGGGGUCCUGUCCCCAUGUAAGGGGAUAUGUACAUUGCUGAGUACGCUGAUAUCUUUUUCAUGGGUAUGAUUUUUUAACAAGAAAGCUAAAUGGUUCUCGUGUAACAUAACUGAUAUAGUUUGGCUGUGUCCCCACCCAAAUCUUAUCUUGAACUGCAGCUCCCAUAAUCCCCAGGUGUUGUGGGAGGGACCCAGUGGGAGGUAAUUGAAUCAUGGGGGUGGUUACCGCCAUGCUGUUCUCGUGAUAGCGAGUGAGUUCUCACGAGAUCUGAUGGUUUUAUAAGGGGCUUUCCCCCUCCUUCGCUCUGCACUUCUCCUUGCUGCCAUGCGAAGAAGGAUGUGUUUGCUUCCCCUUCUGCCAUGAUUGUAAGUUUCCUGAGGCCUCCCCAGCCAUGUUAAACUUUGAGUUAAUUAAACCUCUUUCCUUUAUAAAUUA